UUACAGUAUAGAAUUAUUAAUACUAAAAAUGAUACUUUAAAUUGUAGCAUAAUGUUUGAACAAAAUAUUGUGGGACUACAGAGAAAAGUAUGGCUAACUCUGCCCUGGGGGAAUGGGAAUAAACUUACCAAAAAGCAAAUCUGUUAGUUUUGUACUUUCUCAUACUCUUUGAGAUUUCCUAAAUGCUGAAAUUGAUAAGCACAGAAGAUAGAGACUGAUAUAAUUUUGUAUUAUGUCUAGUCUGCUUUCAAGAACAAGUACUACAGUAUUAGAAGAGACACUGAAGGCCAGGCAUGGGGGCUCACACCUGUAAUCUCAGCACUUUGAGAGGCUGAAGCGGGUGGAUUGCUUGAACUCAUGAGUUCAAGACCAGCCUGGGAAACAUGGCAAAACCCCAUCUCUAAAAAAAUACAAAAAUUAGUCAGGUGUGGUGCUGCACACCUGUAGUCCCCGUUACUCAAGAAGGUGAGGUGGGAGCCUGGAGCUUGAGCUUGGGAGGUGGAGGUUGCAGUGUGCUGAGAUCUUGCCACUGAACUCCUGCCUGAGCAAUAGAGAGCCAGACCUUGUCUCAAAAAGAAAAAAAAAGAAGAAGAAGAAGAAGAAAAGACAGUGAGGAUUGCUGAUGUGGAAAAAUGGAAGAAUUUGGGGGUUUGCUUUAGGUGUAUUAUUAAUCACUUUAAAUGAAGUGCUGGAAUUACAGGCAUGAGCCACCGCACCCAGCAUAAAGAUGGUUUUAAUUCUGUCAUUGAUGUAUUUGUCUUCUGUAUGUGUUUUUUCUUUUAUUCUUUUAUUAUUGUCUUUUUAAAAAUUGAACUUUUUUGUAGUGUAUCAUUUUGAUUUCCCUUUCUUUCACUGUAUAUUUUUAAUGUAUUUUCUUAGUGGUUACCUUGGCGAUUCCAAUUAAUAUCUUAAACUUAUAAACCUAGUUUGAAUAUAUCAAUUUAGUUUCAAGAGUAUACAGAUACUUUGCUUGUGCACAUCUCCAUUCCUCCCCCGUAAUAUUAUAAUUGUCACAAAUUACACCUUUAUACUUUCCAGUAACAUAUUAUAAUUAUUGCUUUAUGAACUUGUUUAUUAAACCAUAUGGGAAAAACAGAAGUUACAAACCAUAUGAAAAGUAUGAAAACAGUGGAUUUAUAUUUAGCUUUAUAGAUACCUUUAUCAGUGGUUUUAAAAAUUUUUUUCACAGUUUUAAGUUACUGUCUAGUGUCCUUUCAUUGCAGCCCAAAUGUCUUUCACAUUUUUUGUAGGGCACUGUACUGACAAAAAAAAAAACUGUGUCAGCUAUUGUUUAACUAGAAAUAUCUUAAUUUCUGCUUGCUUAAAAAAAAUAAUAAUGAUGAUAAUAAUAAUAAUAAUGAUGAUGAUGAUGAUGAUGAUGAUGAUGAUGAUGAUGCUUGAAAGAUAGUUUUGCUGGGUAUAAAAUUCUUGAUUGACAGUUUUUUUUUUUCUUCUCCUUUCCCACUGCUAUCCCACUGCUUUCUAGUCUCCAUAGUUUCUGAGAAGAAAUCUGCUGUUUAUCUUACUGAGGCUCCAUUGUACAUGAAGAGUCACUUCUGUCACUGUUUUCAAAAUUCUUUCUAUUUCUUUAGGUUCUGACAAUUUGACUGUAAUGUUUCUUGUGUGGAGCUCUUUGAGUUUAUCUGCUGGUAGUUUAUUGAGCUUCUAGGAUGUGUGUAUUGAUGUAUUUUGGAAGUAUUUUUCCAUUAAGACUUCAAAUACUUUUCUGUCAUAUUUCCUUCUGGGACACCUAUAUGUGUAUAUUAGUAUGUUUGAUGAUAUCCUACUGGUGCCUCAGGCUCUGUUCAUUUUACUUCAUUUGUUUUUCUGCUUCUCAUAUUGAAGAUAAGACAGCCUCACUGUUCUUAUCUUCAGGUUCACUGAACCUUUCUAACUCCUCCUCAUAUCUGCUUUUGAGCCCCUCUAUUGAGUUUUUCUUACUUCAGUUAGUCUGCUUUUUAGCUCCAGAAUAUGUUUGGUUCCGUUUCAUAAUUUCUGUCUUCCUACUGAUAUUCUCAUUUUUUUCAUACACUGUUUUGCUAAUUUUUUUGUUGAUGGUUUUCUUUAGCUCAUUCAACAUAUUUAAGACAGUAGAUAGUUGAUUUAACACCUUCAACUAAUAACUACAAUGGGCUUUAACGGGAGAGUUUCUGUCAAAUCUUUUUUGUUGUUUCUUUAUUUUCAUUAUGUUAUUUUUUGGUUUUUGAGAACUGUAUUUUGUAUCUUAUUUUUAUUUAUUCAUUUGUUUUGAGGCAGUGUUUCACUCUGUUGCCCAGACUGACGUGCAGGGCAUGAUCAUGGCUCACUGCAGCUUCAACCUCCUGGAUGCCACCAUGCCCAGCUAUUUUUUUUUUUAUUUUUCAUAGAUAUGAGGUCUCAUUAUGUUGCCCAGGCUGGUCUUGAAUUCCUGGGCUCAAGGAAUCCUCCUGCCUCCACCUCCCAAAGUGGAGAGAUUACAUAUGUGGGCUACCAUGCCCGGUGAGAACUAGACCUUUUAAACAUUAUGUUGUGGUAGAUCUGGAAAUGUAAUCCUUCCACUCUCCAGGGAUUGCUGAAUCUUACUUGUUGAGGGUUAAAGUGAUGAUCUGUUUGUGACUUUUGUAAACUGUUUUUGCAAGGUGUGUAGUUUUUGUUAUAAUGUGGUCACUGAAGUUUCUUCUGUUUCCUCUGUGGUCAGCUAUUGACCUGAUAAAGAUUGCUUUCAAUAUCUGGCCUCAAAAAGGAGAAAGAAAAACAAACACACACACAUUGUCUUUAUAUAAUAAAUUCCUUGGAAGUUUCUUAGGUCCGUGGGUAUUGAAGUAGGUGGCCAGCUUUUGUAUUGGUUUCUCAGUAAUCAAAAGCAACAAUGAGAUCAUGCAAUCCAGUAUUUGGAAGACUAGUUCCUUUUUGUGUACCCUGGCUCCAGGAAGCCACACUAGGAAUGCAGGAGGCUGUCUCCAGGCUGCUUCUUGGAGCUGUUGGGAUUGUGGCUGUGGAAUGAGUGAUAGCUGCUACCAUGAAAGAUGGCAAUUCCAUGACAUUUGUCACCCUCUUUUACCAUACGCCAGAGUUCCAAAAUAGUCACUUCAGAUCAUUUCUGUCAAUUGCAUCUUUAGAUGCUAUCUUCUUGGCCUUUUUUUUCCCUCCUUACAAGCAGGAUACCUGAAAUGCCGAAACGUAAUGUAUAUAUUUUUGCAGUCAUUUAGAAAGCAUGAGGGACUGGUAAUUUAAUUCAGAAAGCCUAUUCAAAAACCCAUGUCUAUUUGACUAAUCCAGAAAUUCUGGAAAGAAAUAUACCUGCUAUCACAUCUGGUUAAGACCUUGGUUGUGUUCUGUACAAGUUGCAAACCCACAGGCUCCUUUCCCACCAUUUAGCGGAACCUGAGUUGAGUCACGUGCCUUGGCUACUGAAGAAACCACCAAUCAGGUUUUAGUUUUAUCCAUGUGUGGGUGUUAGUAAUAUCCAAUUAGUAGAAAAAGAGUGUCUUAAUACUGAGGGACCAGUCGGAAAGCUGUCUGACAGGGAGAAAGUCUCAUAUAAAAACAGACAGUAGCUUCCUGUUAUAUCACAUUCCCACUCAGCAGAGAAGCUGUAAGUGGACUCAGGGUCAUUCCCCAGCUCAAGAAAUAAAUAUUCCACAUCUUGAGUAUUAAUGUGUUUUGUUUGUAUUUUUCAGAAACUAUGUAUUCUUUUAAGUCUUAUUAAAGUCAAGAUGAAAUAUGUAAAAAGCCAUUGUUUUUAUUUUAUUUUAUCCAACUGUAUAAUUAUUGUAUGUUUAUAUUGUACAUAUUAGAGCAUAUGAAUAAUGCUUAUUAACUCUGGGACUUUGCUAUAUUAAGAAACUGUUUCUGUUAUCCGUAUUUGGCUGUCAUGUUUUAGUUUACUGUAUGUAGGCUGGAUUUAUUUUCUUUUAACAUGUCUUAAUAUUGGGUUUUGUUUCAGUUCCCUUGAGUAAACGUGUAACUGUUGACCUGUUUAUUCAUGUUGUGUUUUAAAAUCGUCCCCUGAAAAUACAGUAUGCAAAUUAUAUACUAUAUUUAGAUCGGAGGGCUUUUUUCUCCAGUAAAAUUUGGAUUCACCUUUAUAGACUUGGCCAGGAAGUAUAUAUUCUGAACCAGGGAAAGAAAUGCUAAAAACCAAAUUGACAAAGUAGACAGAUGGAAGACCAACAACAUCUGCAUUAAGAAGAUGACGUAGCUUUGCCAAAGACUUAGAAGCUAAGCAGAAAAUGAGCUUAACAUCCUGGUUUUUGGUGAGCAGUGGAGGCACUCGCCACAGGCUGCCACGAGAAAUGAUUUUUGUUGGAAGAGAUGACUGUGAGCUCAUGUUGCAGUCUCGUAGUGUGGAUAAGCAACACGCUGUCAUCAACUAUGAUGCGUCUACGGAUGAGCAUUUAGUGAAGGAUUUGGGCAGCCUCAAUGGGACUUUUGUGAAUGAUGUAAGGAUUCCGGAACAGACUUAUAUCACCUUGAAACUUGAAGAUAAGCUGAGAUUUGGAUAUGAUACAAAUCUUUUCACUGUAGUACAAGGAGAAAUGAGGGUCCCUGAAGAAGCUCUUAAGCAUGAGAAGUUUACCAUUCAGCUUCAGUUGUCCCAAAAAUCUUCAGAAUCAGAAUUAUCCAAAUCUGCAAGUGCCAAAAGCAUAGAUUCAAAGGUAGCAGACGCUGCUACUGAAGUGCAGCACAAAACUACUGAAGCACUGAAAUCCGAGGAAAAAGCCAUGGAUAUUUCUGCUAUGCCCCGUGGUACUCCAUUAUAUGGGCAGCCGUCAUGGUGGGGGGAUGAUGAGGUGGAUGAAAAAAGAGCUUUCAAGACAAAUGGCAAACCUGAAGAAAAAAACCAUGAAGCUGGAACAUCAGGGUGCGGCAUAGAUGCCAAGCAAGUUGAGGAACAAUCUGCAGCUGCAAAUGAAGAAGUACUUUUUCCUUUCUGUAGGGAACCAAGUUAUUUUGAAAUCCCUACAAAAGAAUUCCAGCAACCAUCACAAAUAACAGAAAGCACUAUUCAUGAAAUCCCAACAAAAGACACGCCAAGUUCCCAUAUAACAGGUGCAGGGCAUGCUUCAUUUACCAUUGAAUUUGAUGACAGUACCCCAGGGAAGGUAACUAUUAGAGACCAUGUGACAAAGUUUACUUCUGAUCAGCGCCACAAGUCCAAGAAGUCUUCUCCUGGAACUCAAGACUUGCUGGGGAUUCAAACAGGAAUGAUGGCACCCGAAAACAAAGUUGCUGACUGGCUAGCACAAAACAACCCUCCUCAAAUGCUAUGGGAAAGAACAGAAGAGGAUUCUAAAAGCAUUAAAAGUGAUGUUCCAGUGUACUUGAAAAGGUUGAAAGGAAAUAAACAUGAUGAUGGUACGCAAAGUGAUUCAGAGAACGCUGGGGCUCACAGGCGCUGUAGCAAACGUGCAACUCUUGAGGAACACUUAAGACGCCACCAUUCAGAACACAAAAAGCUACAGAAGGUCCAGGCUACUGAAAAGCAUCAAGACCAAGCUGUUGUAAGUCAAACUGCUUUUAUGAUUGCAUUCUUUGAUGAAGACAAUCCCAGAAAAAGAAGGUCGUAUUCUUUUACUCAAAGUGCGGGAAUCUUGUGUCAGGAAACUACAUAUUCAACACCACAUACAAAACUUGAGAAAGCAAAGUCUCCAACAGCAGAUGCCAAAGUGGUUUCUUUGUCUUUACAGACUAGCUCUGCGCAUCACAGAGGGGGGCAUGGUGUUCCACAUGGGAAAUUGUUAAAACAGAAAUCAGAGGAGCCAUCGGUGUCAAUACCCUUCCUACAAACUGCAUUAUUAAGAAGUUCAGGGAGUCUUGGGCACAGACCAAGCCAGGAGAUGGAUAAAAUGUUAAAAAAUCAAGCAACUUCUGCUACUUCUGAAAAGGAUAAUGAUGAUGACCAAAGUGACAAGGGUACUUAUACCAUUGAGUUAGAGAAUCCCAACAGUGAGGAAGUGGAAGCAAGAAAAAUGAUUGACAAGGUGUUUGGAGUAGAUGACAAUCAGGAUUAUAAUAGGCCUGUUAUCAACGAAAAACAUAAAGAUCUAAUAAAAGAUUGGGCUCUCAGUUCUGCUGCAGCAGUAAUGGAAGAAAGAAAACCACUGACUACAUCUGGAUUUCACCACUCAGAGGAAGGCACAUCUUCAUCUGGAAGCAAACGUUGGGUUUCACAGUGGGCUAGUUUGGCUGCCAAUCAUACAAGGCAUGAUCAAGAAGAAAGGAUAAUGGAAUUUUCUGCACCUCUUCCUUUAGAGAAUGAGACAGAGAUCAGUGAGUCUGGCAUGACAGUGAGAAGUACUGGCUCUGCAACUUCCUUGGCUAGCCAGGGAGAGAGAAGGAGACGAACUCUUCCCCAGCUUCCAAAUGAAGAAAAGUCUCUUGAGAGCCACAGAGCAAAGGUUGUAACACAGAGGUCAGAGAUAGGAGAAAAACAAGACACAGAACUUCAGGAGAAAGAAACACCUACACAGGUAUACCAGAAAGAUAAACAAGAUGCUGACAGACCCUUGAGUAAAAUGAACAGGGCAGUAAAUGGAGAGACUCUCAAAACUGGUGGAGAUAAUAAAACCCUACUUCACUUAGGCAGCUCUGCUCCUGGAAAAGAGAAAAGUGAAACUGAUAAGGAAACUUCUUUGGUAAAGCAAACAUUAGCAAAACUUCAACAACAAGAACAAAGGGAGGAGGCUCAGUGGACACCUACUAAAUUGUCUUCCAAAAAUGUUUCAGGUCAGACAGAUAAAUGUAGGGAGGAAACUUUUAAACAAGAAUCACAACCUCCAGAAAAAAAUUCAGGACAUUCUACAAGCAAAGGAGACAGAGUGGCACAAAGUGAGAGCAAGAGAAGAAAAGCUGAGGAAAUUCUGAAAAGUCAGACUCCAAAGGGAGGAGACAAGAAGGAAUCCUCCAAGUCAUUAGUGCGACAAGGGAGCUUCACUAUAGAAAAACCCAGCCCAAACAUACCCAUAGAACUUAUUCCCCAUAUAAAUAAACAGACUUCCUCUACUCCUUCUUCUUUAGCAUUAACAUCUGCAAGUAGAAUACGAGAAAGAAGUGAGUCUUUGGAUCCUGAUUCUAGUAUGGACACAACCCUUAUUCUAAAAGACACAGAAGCAGUAAUGGCUUUUCUAGAAGCUAAACUACGUGAAGAUAAUAAAACUGAUGAAGGACCAGAUACUCCCAGUUAUAAUAGAGACAAUUCUAUUUCACCAGAAUCUGAUGUAGAUACAGCUAGUACAAUCAGUCUGGUUACUGGAGAAACUGAAAGAAAGUCAACCCAAAAGCGAAAGAGUUUCACUAGCCUCUAUAAAGAUAGGUGUUCCACAGGUUCUCCUUCCAAAGAUGUUACAAAAUCAUCAUCUUCAGGUGCUAGGGAAAAAAUGGAAAAGAAAACAAAAAGUCGUUCCACAGAUGUGGGUUCAAGAGCAGAUGGUCGUAAAUUUGUUCAGUCCAGUGGGAGAAUAAGACAGCCCUCAGUAGACUUAACAGAUGAUGACCAAACCUCUAGUGUACCUCAUUCUGCCAUCUCUGAUAUUAUGUCAUCUGAUCAAGAAACUUACUCUUGUAAACCUCAUGGACGGACUCCACUUACCUCAGCUGAUGAGCAUGUACAUUCCAAACUGGAAGGAAGUAAAGUAACGAAAUCUAAGACUUCUCCGGUGGUAUCUGGUUCAUCUAGUAAAUCAACCACCCUUCCAAGGCCACGACCUACCAGGACUUCCCUCUUGCGCAGAGCACGACUUGGUGAAGCUUCAGACAGUGAACUUGCUGAUGCUGACAAAGCAUCUGUUGCUUCUGAAGUAUCCACAACAAGUUCUACAUCAAAACCUCCCACAGGAAGGCGUAACAUCUCUCGGAUUGAUUUAUUGGCUCAGCCUCGUAGAACACGACUUGGCUCACUGUCAGCUCGUAGUGACUCUGAAGCAACAAUUUCUAGAAGUAGUGCCUCUUCGAGGACCGCAGAAGCCAUCAUUAGAAGUGGAGCCAGACUAGUACCAUCAGAUAAAUUUUCUCCUAGAAUUAGAGCUAACAGUAUCUCUCGACUCUCAGACUCCAAGGUCAAAAGUAUGACCUCAGCUCAUGGCUCUGCUUCAGUAAAUUCAAGAUGGAGGCGCUUUCCUACUGAUUAUGCUUCCACCUCAGAAGAUGAAUUUGGAUCAAACCGUAAUUCCCCUAAACAUACCCGUCUACGUACUUCUCCAGCCCUGAAAACCACUCGCUUGCAGAGCGCUGGAUCAGCAAUGCCUACUAGUUCUUCAUUCAAACACCGGAUUAAAGAGCAGGAAGACUACAUCCGAGAUUGGACUGCUCAUCGAGAAGAGAUAGCCAGGAUCAGCCAAGAUCUUGCUCUCAUUGCUCGGGAGAUCAACGAUGUAGCAGGAGAGAUAGAUUCAGUGACUUCAUCAGGCACUGCCCCUAGUACCACAGUAAGCACUGCUGCCACCACCCCUGGCUCUGCCAUAGACACUAGAGAAGAGGUAGGAGAUCUUCAUGGAGAAAUGCAUAAGUUGGUUGAUCGUGUUUUUGAUGAAAGCCUCAACUUCCGAAAGAUUCCUCCAUUAGUUCAUUCCAAAACACCAGAAGGAAACAACGGUCGAUCUGGUGAUCCAAGACCUCAAGCAGCAGAGCCUCCCGAUCACUUAACAAUUACAAGGCGGAGAACCUGGAGCAGGGAUGAAGUCAUGGGAGAUAAUCUGCUGCUGUCAUCCGUCUUUCAGUUCUCUAAGAAGAUAAGACAAUCUAUAGAUAAGACAGCUGGAAAGAUCAGAAUAUUAUUUAAAGACAAAGAUCGGAAUUGGGAUGACAUAGAAAGCAAAUUAAGAGCCGAAAGUGAAGUCCCUAUUGUGAAAACCUCAAGCAUGGAGAUUUCUUCUAUCUUACAGGAACUGAAAAGAGUAGAAAAGCAGCUGCAAGCAAUCAAUGCUAUGAUUGAUCCUGAUGGAACUUUGGAGGCUCUGAACAACAUGGGAUUUCCCAGUGCUAUGUUGCCAUCUCCACCGAAACAGAAGUCCAGCCCUGUGAAUAACCACCACAGCCCGGGUCAGACACCAACACUUGGCCAACCAGAAGCUAGGGCUCUUCAUCCUGCUGCUGUUUCAGCCGCAGCUGAAUUUGAGAAUGCUGAAUCUGAGGCUGAUUUCAGUAUACAUUUCAAUAGAUUCAACCCCGAUGGGGAAGAGGAAGAUGUUACAGUACAAGAAUGACUUUCUCUUGAUUGUUGAAAAAUCAUUACCUGUGGAAUGGCUAGGAAUAUUGGAAGCAGCAUAGUGUUGAUGUACGCAAAACAAGACAGCUUGGUCAGCUACAAUCUUGGAAUCCCUGUCUUCUUAAUUUUAUUUAUUUAUUUUUGACGUAUAAUGUAGUAUAUCAAUCCUUUCAAACUAUUUAGAUAACCACUUGAUGCACAAAUAGGAAAAAGCAGAUUGUGGCAGUGUCGCCUUUUGUGGUUUUAUGAUUUUCAAAUUGAAUUUAAUGAUUACACCCUUUCCCUUCAUAGAUCUUUUUUCUUUUUUUUAAGCCAUGCUGUGACCUACAAGCAAACUAAAUAGCCAACAUUUCUGAACCCCUAAGUCUCCUGUGCCAAGCUGCUCCCUGAAAUGGACUUCUUCAUCUGUACAGAUUUGUUAAACCAUUCUAUUUGCUUCUUAAUAAUAGGAUUUAUAUUAGUACUCAUUACCAUUGGACACAAUGACAUAAGUACUCUCCACAGUAAAGCAGACCUUUCACAACAGUCACUCUGUGUCCUAAAAUUUUCCAACAUAGAUGUGAUUUAUAUAACUUUGUUGAUACGUAAAUUGUCUUGGGGUUUACGGAAAUUAACUAUUAUGUUUGCACUAAGAUUUGCUGGGAGUGGUAGGUGGACAUAUCUAUAUAUCAAUAAGGACUAACCGUCUUUUUUGUACAUAGGAGAUUGAUAAUACUGUAUUUGUUUUAAGCCCACAGUGUUUUACUCCACUUUCAAAAAGAUCAAUUUGGCACUUUUUUUCAUUUUUUUUAAUGGAAAUAAGAUUUGGUCUCUCAUUUUAGGUUAAAUGAUAACUAGAAAGAUUAAACUAGACAGAUAGUUUAGGUGGAGUAUAUUUUUAAAACUCAGAACAUGUAUAUUGGUCCUGUGUUACCAAGUUUAUAUGUGACAGUUGAAAAAGAAAUUCCCUUGAAAUGAUCAUGAGGUUAAAAUUUUCUUCAUUAGGGGACUUGGAGAACCAGUAGUCGUAAGAUUAGUUGAUAGUUUCACUCCCAAGCAAUGAAUUGCUUCUGUGUGUUUCCCUGUAGGACUCAAUAGUAAAUGCUGUCUGUCUUACACAUUUAUAAGGACCCUGCAAGACGACGACAAAGGCCUUUGGCCUGUGCUACUAAACAAGAAGCCUAUGAAAAAUUUCUUCUUUAAACUUGUUUUUUCUCUUUCCAGUAAGUUCACAUUUGGAUAAUUUUAAAAAGAAAAGUAAUUACCUUUGUGUUUCCAGAACACUAUAAUUGGGGUGUAUCUUAAUUCAGUUAAAUAUUAUUAGUAGACCUGGAUUUUCCCCCUUGACCCCAUCAGUCUAUAAAGGUUAAACUGCAACUUUUAUGAAAUGGUCUUUAAUAUUUCCACAAUAAUCCUGUGCUAUAUUUGUUUUAAGAAACAAAGUAACUCUAUACACUUCAAGACUUUACAGGAUUUUUUAAAUCCUGUAUUGUUGGAUCAAUUAAUAAAGAUGCAAAAAAACUUUAUAGAGAUGUAAAAACAAAACUAUAAUGGAUCUCCUAUUUUUCUUUAAAUACAAAAAAAAAAAGGUAAAUGAACUAUUCUCCUUGUAAAGCUAAAUUCCCCAUUCUGUCUAAUAAAGGAAGACUGAAAAAAGGUUUUAAAGAACAUAAAUGGAAAGAUACAAAUGCUUUGAAGGAAUAAACGAAAUGUUAAAACAGGGUCAAUCCAUUUGAAGAAAAAGUUGGACAAAAUAAUCAGCAUUGCUCCCUCUUUUAUUUAAUAUUUGGGUACUGAUUAUAUCCACAUGGAAGUAGAAGGUAAGGAGUUUAGGAAAAUACUAGAAUCUACUCUGCUUACAUUCUUGUUUAAGUGUUUACACAGUUUGGUUCAAUUAUAAACAUUUGGCCUUUUACUAUGUUAUUUUUAUUUUGUAUGAAUACAUUAUCCUCCUUAUUUAUUUUUGUUACAUUUAUUACUUAUGUUAUUUUGUUAUGCAUUUACAACUCCAUUUUUAAAUAAAGUGUUUCUGGAACUUUA